AGUAAGGAGAACCAGCCAGGCAGCACAUCACAGCGGGAGGAGCUGUCCCAGGUGGCCCAGCUCAGCAAUGGCAAUGGGGGUCCCCAGAGUCAUUCUGCUCUGCCUCUUUGGGGCUGCGCUCUGCCUGACAGGGUCCCAAGCCCUGCAGUGCUACAGCUUUGAGCACACCUACUUUGGCCCCUUUGACCUCAGGGCCAUGAAGCUGCCCAGCAUCUCCUGUCCUCAUGAGUGCUUUGAGGCUAUCCUGUCUCUGGACACCGGGUAUCGCGCGCCGGUGACCCUGGUGCGGAAGGGCUGCUGGACCGGGCCUCCUGCGGGCCAGACGCAAUCGAACGCGGACGCGCUGCCGCCAGACUACUCGGUGGUGCGCGGCUGCACAACUGACAAAUGCAACGCCCACCUCAUGACUCAUGACGCCCUCCCCAACCUGAGCCAAGCACCCGACCCGCCGACGCUCAGCGGCGCCGAGUGCUACGCCUGUAUCGGGGUCCACCAGGAUGACUGCGCUAUCGGCAGGUCCCGACGAGUCCAGUGUCACCAGGACCAGACCGCCUGCUUCCAGGGCAAUGGCAGAAUGACAGUUGGCAAUUUCUCAGUCCCUGUGUACAUCAGAACCUGCCACCGGCCCUCCUGCACCACCGAGGGCACCACCAGCCCCUGGACAGCCAUCGACCUCCAGGGCUCCUGCUGUGAGGGGUACCUCUGCAACAGGAAAUCCAUGACCCAGCCCUUCACCAGUGCUUCAGCCACCACCCCUCCCCGAGCACUACAGGUCCUGGCCCUGCUCCUCCCAGUCCUCCUGCUGGUGGGGCUCUCAGCAUAGACCGCCCCUCCAGGAUGCUGGGGACAGGGCUCACACACCUCAUUCUUGCUGCUUCAGCCCCUAUCACAUAGCUCACUGGAAAAUGAUGUUAAAGUAAGAAUUGCACUCCUGUCCCUCUGGCCUUCCAUCUCUCCCGCCCUUGUGCCCCACAACCUGGCCAACAGUACUGGAAGAAACUGGACACAGUCACCAGCAUCCCCGGGGAGGGCAAAACAGCCAUGUCGUGCCCCGAUGAAGAGCAAUUCUGAUCACAGCUGUUACUCACUGAGCACCAGCCAGGCACCAGGCACCCCAUAACACGGCUUCCUGUGCUCUCCCUCCAGAGCCUGUCGCAGCUCUAGGAGGGAGCUAUACAAUGAUGUCUUUAUUAGUGUCAUCAUGAGAAGCCCAAUAAGCAGUAUGCCCUAACAGUUAGUAGGCCAGGCUCUGGAGCUAAGCUGCAUGGGUUCAAAUCCCAGCUCCACCAUUCAGCCUGCAGAGACCAUGAGCGAGUUACUUAAGCCAGGCUCUGGAGCUAAGCUGCAUGGGUUCAAAUCCCAGCUCCAGCAUUCAGCCUACAGAGACCAUGGGUGAGUUACUUAAGCCAGGCUCUGGAGCUAAGCUGCAUGGGUUCAAAUCCCAGCUCCACCAUUCAGCCUGCAGAGACUGUGGGUGAGUUACUUGAGCUCUCUGUGCCAAUAUUUUCUCACCUAUAAGGUGGAGGUGAAAAUAAACUCUAUAACAUGACAAGAACUACUUCACAGUAGUUGCAGUGAGGAUUCAACGAGAUGAACAUUUAGUACUUGGGACACAGCAGUGGCCCAGUGUAAAUGGGCUACUUGUCAUAAGCCCUAAGUCACAGGUCAACAAACUGAGAGGCAAAAGCACUUGGUUGAGCUUGUGUAUCUAGUGAGUAUGGAUUCAGGGACCAGAUUCCCAGCCCCACGAACUGCUAAGCAACCCCACCUCCUAAACACAUGAGUGCCGAUUAACUUCACAGAAAAACACACAAGGCAAAGUUCAGCGAGGUGAAAUUCUCCAAGCUAUAAAGAUCAGGGAAGACUUCCUGGAGGAAUUCACCCUUGAGCAAAAUCCUAAAGGAUCAAUAGUAGCUGGCAAAAAGAAGCAGGAGGAAGCGCAUUCUAGGUAGAGGAGACAGCCUGGACAAAGGUCUGAGGGAGGAAGGAGCACAAGGAGUGCAGGACACUUUCAUGAGUGCAGGACACUUUCAUAACUGCAUGAACUUCAUAGAGAUGGGAUCCUUUAGCAUGUUCUCUGUGCACAUGCUUGACCAUGUUCUUUCACAUGCUUUUUGCCACUUGAUCUUUCCAGCAACUCAGUGAGAGAAGCAAAAAAGUAAGUUGCAUCCUGCUAUUGUCUGAAUGUUUGUGUCUCCCCAAAAUUCAUCUUUUGAAACCUAAUUACCAAAGUGAUAUUACUGGGAGGUGGGGCCUUUGGGAGGUGGUGAGAUCAUGAGGGUGGAGCCCCCAUGAAUAGGAUUAGUGCCCUUAUAAAAGAGGCCCUGGAGAGCUGCCUUGCCCCUUCCACCACAUGAGAACACAGCCAGCAGGUGCCUAUAAGCAAGAAAGUGGGUUCUCACCAGCCAUCGAAUCUGCUGGUGCAUUGAUUGCAGACUUCCCAGACUCCAGAGCUAUGAGACAUAAAUUUCUGUUGUGUAUAAGCCA